UCCAAACAGUGGAGGACAAUGAAAGAUAACAGAUACUUUAGUAUGCGUUCAUGUACUGGCUGGAACAUGUUCAUGCUCUGGCAGUGACUUUAGCUUUUCCUUAGAAAGCAUGGGGAUAUUAAGUUAUUUAAAAGUAUUCUUUAGAUCUAAAGUCUAAAGGCAUCUACCCAGAUUAAUUUUUUAAUAUUUUCUGUAUAGUUUCCUGAUGGUAUUAGAAGCAGGAAGUAGUAUGGAGAUAAGGAGCAUAUUUAUUGAAUGCCUACUAUGUGCCAAGCACUUUGCUUAACAUUAUGAUUAAUUUUUGACUUCUCAAAACCUUGUGAUUUAGUUAGUACCUAUCCAUUUUAUAGAUGUAGAGAGCAAGAAUCAUUGAUACUAAUUAACUUGCCCAGCUUUAUGCAGUUAGUGAAAAGAAGUUAAAACCCAGGUAUGUUGGAUCCCAAGGCCCAAGUUCUUGACCACUGUCUUCUAAUCAACAAAAGCUAUAUACUUAAGAAAACAAGGGUGAAGAAUGAGGAUACUAAUACAUUGGUAUCACUGUACUUGACAUUGUGGUUUAUGUUUCAAAUACUGGUUCUGUAGUCUUAAAGGAGUAUAUUUAUUUGCAAAUGAAAGUAGCAAGCUCACGAUGGCUUCCUCCAUGGUUUAAGAGGAUAAUGAGAGAGAUCAAUAGUUGUUGUCUUGUAGCCAAGCGGUACAGGGGAGAACUGGAAAGGUAGGUUCCCAUUUGCUCUGUCCUGGAGGAGAUAGUCAAUGAGAGUAUAGCCAAGUAAAAUUAUUACAAAUGUUCAUAAGUACUUUGAAGGAAACAAGUAGGGGUUGAGGUAGAGACCAGCAGGAUAAGGAAUGUUGCAUACAUAAGACGUGGGAAAUAGGAAUGGCUCAUGUGAGGAAGUGACAUAGGACCUGAGCCAUGAAGGCUGAGGAGCCAGGUCUUAGAGCUGAGUGCUGCUGUCAGUUAUCAGAGGAGCCCUGAAUAGGCCAUACUCCUCCAGGGAUGGGGCAUAGAGUCCUAGGCUUCUUCAUUCCUGGCAGAGAGUAGGCACCAUGCCGGGCACAUGGCUGGCCCUGAUGUAUAUUUGCUGAAUGAAUUUUGCAAAUCCCUGCAAAGAGCAUUUCCUUAUGUACCUGCUUAUACGGUCAUCUGUGUUGAUGUAGUGCAGCCAGGUACUUGUCUACUUAAACUUUUCAUUACAGAAAUUUUUAAACACAAAACAGAGUCUAGAAUAAUGAAUCUCCAUGCAUCCAUAUCUACAUUCAACAAUUAUUAAUAUUUUUUCAAUCUUAUUUUAUCUAACCUCUACUUCAUUUUUUUCUCCCUAUGGUAUUUUCCAGCAAGUCCCAGGCAUCAUAUCUUUACAAUUGUAAAUACUUUAAUAUGCGUUUCACACUGAUGAGGGCAUUUUUAUUUACAUAGCCUCAGGUCACUAUCACACUUAGAAUUAAUAAGGACUAAUCUUCUGAUCUUUUAAAAAUUUAAUAAAGCUAAAUACAAUUUAUUAACAAAUUAUGAUGGAAUUAGCAUCUAUAAAUGUGCCUGGAUGCAGUUGCUAUUUCCUUUUAAAUUCUUCUCAUGUUUGUGACUUGACUGUCCAAUGACUGUAAUUUCUUACUCUCUCUCCAAAGCUAGCAACCAAACAUCAACUUUUCGUUAAAAACAAGCAAAAAAAAAAGUGGCCCAAGAGGAGCGUCUACACUGCAACUGACUUAGAAAGCUGCUUGACAGAACCUCCUCUCUUUAUUGGUCCCUGUGGUGGCAGAUGGUAUUAAAUCUGUACAUGUGUCAGAAACAUUAUUUUUCAAAAGUUUGCUCUGAUAUUUUUCCUCCAGACAUCAUCGGAUGUUGGUUCUGUCUUCAUAAAUUGCAAGUGGAAUUGAGCAUCGGUAGACUUUGGACAAUCUUCUGUCACUCAGAACUGGCUGCUAUGUACUCAACACUGGGAAUCUAGAAAAAUACAGAUCUUUGAAAUCAUUACUGCUGACAAAGAAAAAGGAAGUCCCAGUGACACCUCUUAACAUCAUGACAACCUGACUCACCGACCACUUUCACUUUUUCAAAAAACCGUGCAGUGUUAGUUUGGCUUUAACAUCUCUGUACCCCUCAUUCAUUAUUUAAUCUUAUUUUGCUUUGUUCAGACAAGCUAUCUGGGCUAUUGUGAAGCUUCACACAGCCAAUUACCUCAAGGUGUUUAGUUCAUUUAUUAUUUAAAGCAUAAAUCUUGUACAGGUUGUCCAUUGACGACCCUCUGAGUAGAUGGAGUAAAUGCCUUUCAUCCUGGCGGCCUCAGUCAGUGCUCACAGACCUGCUUGCUGAGCUUGGCAGGCCAGGCGAGAGCUGGAGCAUGUAAGAUAGCAGAGUUUACAAGCAUUGAGAAAGGAGAAAUCCCGAGAUGCUGCUCGCUCCCGCCGGGGAAAAGAAAACUUUGAGUUCUAUGAAUUGGCCAAGUUGUUGCCUCUUCCUGCAGCCAUUACCAGCCAGCUCGACAAGGCAUCCAUCAUUCGACUUACAAUUAGCUAUCUGAAAAUGAGGGACUUUGCUAACCAGGGGGACCCUCCGUGGAACUUGCGAAUGGAAGGCCCUCCACCUAACACAUCAGUAAAAGUUAUAGGUGCACAGCGAAGGAGAAGCCCCAGUGCACUAGCCAUUGAAGUAUUUGAAGCACAUUUGGGAAGCCACAUUUUGCAGUCCCUGGAUGGCUUUGUAUUUGCACUAAAUCAGGAAGGAAAAUUUUUGUACAUUUCCGAAACAGUCUCCAUCUACCUAGGCCUCUCACAAGUGGAGCUGACAGGCAGCAGUGUCUUUGACUAUGUCCACCCCGGAGAUCACGUGGAGAUGGCUGAGCAGCUGGGCAUGAAGCUCCCCCCUGGGCGGGGUCUCCUGUCACAGGGCACUGCUGAGGACGGAGCCAGCUCAGCAUCUUCCUCCUCUCAGUCGGAGACCCCCGAGCCAGUGGAGUCAACCAGCCCCAGUCUGCUAACCACUGACAACACUCUUGAGCGUUCCUUUUUCAUCCGAAUGAAAUCUACUCUGACCAAACGCGGUGUGCACAUCAAAUCAUCAGGAUAUAAGGUGAUUCACAUAACAGGCCGGCUACGCCUGAGAGUGUCGCUGUCCCACGGGAGGACCGUCCCCAGCCAAAUCAUGGGUCUCGUGGUUGUUGCGCAUGCCUUGCCUCCCCCUACGAUCAAUGAAGUCAGAAUUGACUGCCAUAUGUUCGUCACUCGAGUAAAUAUGGACCUCAAUAUCAUUUACUGUGAAAAUAGGAUUAGUGAUUAUAUGGAUCUGACCCCUGUAGAUAUCGUAGGGAAGAGAUGCUACCACUUCAUCCAUGCUGAAGACGUGGAGGGCAUCAGGCACAGUCACUUGGACUUGCUGAAUAAGGGUCAGUGUGUGACAAAGUACUAUCGCUGGAUGCAGAAGAACGGAGGAUAUAUUUGGAUACAGUCCAGUGCCACCAUAGCUAUUAAUGCCAAGAAUGCAAAUGAAAAGAAUAUCAUCUGGGUGAAUUACCUUCUUAGCAAUCCUGAGUACAAGGACACACCCAUGGACAUCGCACAGCUCCCCCAUCUGCCGGAGAAAACUUCCGAAUCCUCGGAGACAUCCGACUCUGAGUCAGACUCUAAAGACACCUCAGGUAUUACAGAGGACAACGAGAACUCCAAGUCCGACGAGAAGGGGAACCAGUCCGAGAACAGCGAAGACCCGGAGCCCGACCGGAAGAAGUCGGGCAACGCGUGUGACAACGACAUGAACUGCAACGACGACGGCCACAGCUCCAGUAACCCGGACAGCCGCGACAGCGACGACAGCUUCGAGCACUCGGACUUUGAGAACCCCAAGGCGGGCGAGGACGGCUUCGGUGCUCUGGGCGCGAUGCAGAUCAAGGUGGAGCGCUACGUGGAGAGCGAGUCGGACCUGCGGCUGCAGAACUGCGAGUCACUCACGUCCGACAGCGCCAAGGACUCGGACAGCGCAGGCGAGGCGGGCGCGCAGGCCUCCAGCAAGCACCAGAAGCGCAAGAAAAGGCGGAAACGGCAAAAGGGCGGCAGCGCCAGCCGCCGGCGCCUGUCCAGCGCGUCGAGCCCAGGCGGCCUGGACGCGGGCCUGGUGGAGCCCCCGCGGCUGCUGUCCUCCCCCAACAGUGCCUCGGUGCUCAAGAUCAAGACGGAGAUCUCAGAACCCAUCAAUUUCGACAAUGACAGCAGCAUCUGGAACUACCCGCCCAACCGGGAGAUCUCCAGGAACGAGUCCCCCUACAGCAUGACCAAGCCCCCCAGCUCUGAGCACUUCCCGUCCCCGCAGGGCGGCGGCGGUGGGGGUGGCGGUGGCGGGGGGCUGCACGUGGCCAUUCCCGACUCGGUCCUCACCCCGCCCGGCGCCGACGGCGCGGCCGCCCGCAAGACUCAGUUCGGCGCCUCGGCCACCGCGGCCCUGGCCCCCGUCGCCUCCGACCCGCUGUCACCCCCGCUCUCGGCGUCCCCGCGGGACAAGCACCCCGGGAACGGCGGCGGGGGCGGGGGCGGGGGCGGCGGCGCGGGGGGCGGCGGCCCCAGCGCGUCCAACUCCUUGCUGUACACUGGGGACCUGGAGGCGCUGCAGAGGUUGCAGGCGGGCAACGUCGUGCUCCCGCUGGUGCACAGGGUGACCGGGACCCUGGCCGCCACCAGCACGGCCGCGCAGAGGGUCUACACCACGGGCACCAUCCGCUACGCGCCCGCCGAGGUGACCCUGGCCAUGCAGAGCAACCUGCUGCCCAACGCGCACGCUGUUAACUUCGUGGACGUUAACAGCCCCGGCUUUGGCCUCGACCCCAAGACGCCCAUGGAGAUGCUCUACCACCACGUGCACCGGCUCAACAUGUCAGGACCGUUCGGCGGCGCAGUGAGCGCAGCUAGCCUGACGCAGAUGCCCGCCGGCAACGUGUUCACCACGGCCGAGGGACUCUUCUCCACGCUGCCCUUCCCCGUCUACAGCAACGGCAUCCACGCGGCACAGACUCUGGAGCGCAAGGAGGACUGAGGCGCCGCCCGUCCUGGGCCCGGCCAGGCCCCGCUUGGAGGAGGCAUCGUCGGCAUUUUCGUUUAGACCUUUAAUUCUAGCACUUUGAAUUCGAGCAGGUCAGCGUCUUCUCUCGCCACGACGGUCCCCAUUCCACCCCCUCUUUCUUUCACCUGACUUAUUCUUUCGUGUAAAGAUAUGUUUAUUUUUUGCCUUCAGAGGGUCAGACGACCAGUUGCCUGCCGUUUUGUCUUCUUCUAAGGUGUGUGUUGGGUUGUUUUGCUUUCCUUUGCAUCUUUAUUAAGAUGUCUUUCAUGUGUAUAUGCCUCUGCCAUAGAAUACUCAGUCUUGUGGUCAAGAGAGUUCUCAAGUGACAACCAUUGGGGUUUCUUCAUAAAGAUCUUGAUAUGAUCAAGAUGGAAAGAGACAAGCAUAAACAAUGUGCCCUGUUUGACUAAGUCAAAUGAAAUAGGGUGGUUUUUGUUUCUGUUCCUAAUUCCUUUAAAAAAUAGGGGGAAUAGUAUUUUAGAAUUUUAUGCAGAAUUUAAUUCUCUUUUUACGGUUAAGAUUUUAAGAUUUUCUUACUUGCACAUAAAAAUAAUUUGGGUUCUUAAACUUAAUUUCUGGCCUGUGACUAGAAUGUUUAAAAAAAAAAAAGUCGGACUAAAUGUUAAUUACUGAAACAUUAACUUAAUUUCUAAAACCAUGGUGCUAUCAUUUAUUAAUCUGUAAUGUCUUCAUACAAAAUGCAGCUCCUGGGCUGGGUUUUGGGGGAAAAAAAAAAAAUGUGUUCUGUCCUGGUCUGGAGUCCGUUGCUGCAGUCUCCUUGGUUAGUUAAGACAAAGCCCUCAUUAACGUUUGCUGCAGGACUUAAAAUUUUUUACCUCCCAACUAACAAACAUAGCCUCACAUUAAAUUUAAUGGGUCAGUAAAGCCCCUUUUAAAGGGGCUGCUGGAAAACUCAAUCAAACUGAUUUGAGGAGCAGUUUAGGUACAUACUGCCUUUUGUUUAGCUUUUUGUUUUCCUUACUCAGUCUAACUGAGGCUAAUUUUGCAACUUCAAUAACACUUCGGAGUAAAAGAAGGAAAAUAUUUAACAUGUUUUUGGUUUUUUUCAUUUCUUGCUUAAAACAAAAAGGAAGGUUGUAUUUGGGGGGACUGGUUUGAUUUGAUGGAAUUUCUUUCCCUUUGGUUCUUAUUUCUGGGUUGAAACCAAUAAGUUUUAAAACUAAAGAAUGGGUUAAUAAGCUUCAGACAGAUAACUGCAACUGAAAACUGCACAUUAAGUAAAAAAAAAAAAAAAGAAAAAAAAAAGAAAAAGAAAAAGAAAAAAAAUCCUAUUUUGUCUUUGUUGCCAGAAAUCAGUGUGGUGUCAAACACUCCAAAUGACUGUCAAGUAUAAAUUCUUCUUCCACUUCAUUUUUGGCAGCUGUUUGUUAAGGCAUCUAAUAACAGAUGUGAGAACUGUAAUGUGUACAAUGUGUAUGUGUCCUUGGCUGUCAGUCCCAUUGCAGUUUCAAUGUGUGUUUCUAUAUGCAGUAUAUACUAAGCUAAUGUAGUUGUUUUGUCCUUUGUCUUAUCUGUGCUCUAUCUCUAGUCCGGAGUGGUACAGUCCCAUUCCUGCAGUCCUAGUGAAUCAGUGAUUCUUGGGGGUUAGUGGGUUUUGUGUGGUGGCCUUCCUCUGUAAUGUCACCCUAUGCUGCUUCUACUGUCUGUGAAUCUUCCGUUUUACCUUUUAAAAUUCCUGCUGUUGCUUUGCUGGUGUAUAUUCUCCCUACCUCUCCUCUCUUUCCCUCCCUUUCCCAUCUCCCCCUCUCCCUCCUCUUCAUUCCUUCCCCAUCCCCAAAAUCUCUUUCAUUCUCAGAGAUAAAAAGACUCUUAACUAGCUCAAGGUUAAUGGAGCCAUUUUUCCCACAACGGAAUUCUGGGUAUGACUCUGUCUUCUGGAGUGCAACACAAAGCACUGAAGAAUAAUGCUCAGAUAUAUUAAAUAAAUUGAUGCCAUAUAGCCUCAGUUGUUAACAUUCCCAGAGUCCCUUGUGCUCUACCUAUAAGCAGUGGGUGCUUUUCUUUGGUUUCCUUUCAGGUUGGCUGAUGGAGCAAUAUAUAAAGCAAUUACCAGUGAGACAGAAAAUUCUUUCAAAGGUCAACCAACAUUUUUAAGAAACAAAAUGGGAGGGGAUAAUGGAAUCUAGAAUUGUCAUAUAUAUUUGUUUACUUGUGCAAUGCUAAUAUAGUAACUCGGCUGUCCUUUGAAUAUCACUGUGUUGAGUAGAUUCCUCUAGGACCUUUGAUUUCAUGAGUUGGGCCCAAACCGUGGUGGAAUAAUAACAAAAAGAAGUUAAAUGCCACAAAUUUUAAUAGUGAGCUUACUUGAAGGAUUUAAGUAGGUUUAGGAGGUGAAGAAGGCCGAUGGAGAAAUUUACAGAUUAAUUUUGGAAGCUCUACUCUAGCUAUCGAACAAUCAAAGGAAUGCACCUAUCAGCUACAAAGAACAGCUAGACAGCUGUUUUUUUUCUUUUAUAAAUGUUUCUGUGUUGUGUCAAAAUGAUUUCUGGUGAUUUAAACUAACAGAUAAUCACAGCUGCUGUCUAAAUUCAUAGUGUUGAAAAUUACAAAAUGAAAAAAAAAAAAAAAACACUUCAUUACCUGUGAAGACUGUGUCUGUGUUUUUAACUAUUUCUUGUACAAAUAUAUGAAAACUUUUAUGAGGAGACUGGUGCCAAGUAGCUGAAUAAUGGGGAAAGGGAUAUUCUGUUCGUAAAAAUCUUAGCAGUGUUACCAACUCUACGAUAUAUAUAUAAAAAAAUAAUUAAAACGUUACAAAGCGACAGCUAUGGUACAUUUGUUUUGUGUGAAGCUAACCGGACCUAACUUCCUGAGUGCCUGGCUUAUUUUGAAACAUUUUUUUUCAUUGACCAUUGAUAAUGCUGCAAAUCAGAAAUGUACAUACUUCAUUUACAACAGGGUUCUUUUUAUACUUUUGUAGAUUCUCAUACAUGUCACAUACAUGGUUGUCUUUAUGUAACUUAAUUUUUUCAUCCGCAGGUGCCAUUUUCAUAAUAAACUUCUCUUGGAUUUGUUA